GCUUGGUGCGCCCGCUGUCACCGCCAUGGCUGCCCCGUGUUUGCUGCGGCAAGGACGAGCCGGGGCGCUGAAGACUAUGCUCCAGGAAGCCCAGGUGUUUCGAGGACUUGCUUCUACGGUUUCUUUGUCUGCGGAAUCAGGGAAGAGUGAAAAGGGUCAGCCACAGAAUUCCAAGAAGCAAAGUCCACCAAAAAAUGUAGUGGAACCAAAGGAGAGGGGCAAGCUCCUAGCCACCCAGACAGCAGCUGAAUUGUCUAAAAACUUAUCUUCACCCAGUUCUUACCCGCCAGCUGUGAAUAAGGGCAGGAAGGUAGCUAGUCCCAGUCCCAGUGGCAGCGUGCUAUUCACAGAUGAAGGGGUUCCGAAAUUUUUGUCAAGAAAGACUUUGGUAGAGUUUCCACAGAAAGUUCUGUCUCCAUUCAGAAAACAGGGCUCUGAUUCAGAAGCUCGUCAGGUGGGUCGGAAAGUGACGUCGCCUUCGUCUUCAUCCUCUUCCAGCUCCUCUGAUUCUGAAUCUGAUGAUGAGGCUGACGUUUCAGAGGUCACUCCUCGAGUGGUGAGCAAAGGCAGAGGGGGGCUUCGAAAACCAGAGGCCUCUCAUUCCUUUGAAAACAGAGCCCCCCGAGUUACAGUAUCAGCAAAAGAGAAAACCUUGCUGCAGAAGCCGCAUGUGGACAUUACUGAUCCAGAGAAGCCCCACCAGCCAAAGAAGAAAGGGUCCCCUGCUAAGCCAUCAGAAGGCAGGGAAAAUGCGAGACCAAAAACCACAAUGCCCAGAUCUCAAGUAGAUGAAGAGUUUUUGAAGCAAAGUUUAAAGGAAAAACAAUUGCAGAAAACAUUUAGAUUAAAUGAAAUAGAUAAAGAAAGCCAAAAGCCAUUUGAAGUUAAAGGACCCUUACCUGUCCACACAAAAUCAGGGUUGUCUGCGCCACCGAAGGGCAGCCCAGCGCCUGCUGUGUUGGCAGAAGAGGCCAGAGCAGAGGGGCAGCUGCAAGCCAGUCCUCCUGGGGCGGCAGAGGGGCAUCUGGAAAAACCCGUGCCAGAGCCCCAGCGCAAGGCGGCCCCUCCCCUGCCCAGAAAGGAAACCUCAGGGACGCAGGGAAUAGAAGGCCACCUGAAGGGUGGACAGGCAAUCGUGGAAGAUCAGAUACCACCAAGCAAUUUGGAGACAGUUCCUGUUGAGAAUAACCACGGUUUCCAUGAAAAGACAGCAGCGCUGAAGCUUGAGGCCGAGGGCGAGGCCAUGGAAGAUGCAGCCGCGCCAGGGGACGACCGAGGCGGCACACAGGGUGUCCCUACACCACACCGAAGAUACUCACCUUGUGGAGAUUGGAAGGAUGCCAGCUCUUUAAAGCCAGCCCCAGUGCCUGCUGAGCCGUUUGACAACACUACCUACAAGAACCUGCAGCAUCAUGACUACAGCACGUACACCUUCUUAGACCUCAACCUCGAACUCUCAAAAUUCAGGAUGCCUCAGCCCUCCUCAGGCCGGGAGUCACCUCGACACUGAGGGCCCUCGGUGUGAAGAUGAACCUUCCACCGUCUUCACUGCAUCCUGGAGUGCAAAAAUAAAAUCCACUCAAGAGUCACAAGGCCCGCUGUGCAUAAUCGGUUUCACUUUUACCUUUUUUUUUUUUUUUUUUUUUUUGAGACAGGGUCUCACUCUGUCACCCAGGCUGGAGUGCAGUGGCACAUUCUCGGCUCACUGCAACUUCCGCCUCCUGGGUUCAAGUGAUUCUCCCACCUCAGCCUCCCAAGUAGGUGGGAUUACAGGUACUCACCACCAGGUCCAGCUAACUUUUGUAUUUUUAGUAGAGACAGGGUUUCACCAUGUUGGCCAGGCUGGUCUCGAACUCCUGACCUCAGAUGGUCUGCCCACCUCCGCCUCCCAAAGUGCUGGGAUUACAGGCGUGAGCCACUGCGCCCGGCCACUUUCACACUUUUUACAGUGAGUGGUGAAUUAGCAACAGUAACACUGAUUAUCCAACAUAUAUUUUGGAAUAUCUACUAUGUGCAAGGAAUUUUUCUUAAACUCUAAGGUUAUGAAUCACUGGGCAAAUCCAUAUAAUUAGAGAAUUUUAAGUGCUUUAGAGCGGUGUGAUUCUACUGUGCUCAGCCUAGUCAAUUUCGCAUUAAACUGAUUAUCAGCUGAGUAUCAAUAAUGUAAUAGUGACUUCUUUUAUUUUUUUUGAGAUGGAGUCUCUGUUUCCCAGGCUGGAGUCCAGCGGCACAAUCUAAACUCACUGCAACCUCCGCCUCCUGGGUUCAAGUGAUUCUCCUGCCUUACUUAGCCUCUUGAGUAGCUGGUACUACAGGCUCACGCCACCAUGCCUGGCUAAUUUUUUUUGUAUUUUUAGUAGAGAUGGGGUUUCACCAUCUUGGCCAGGCUGGUCUUAAACUCCUGACCUCAUGAUCUACCUGCCUCAGCCUCCCAAAAUGCUGGCAUUAUAGGCGUGAGCCACUGCACCCAGCCAGUAAUAGUGACUUCUAAUCCUACAGCCCUGGUUUUUGAUCAUUAGAAACAGGAGUUUUGGCCAGGUGCAGUGGAUAAUUCCUGUAAUCCCAGCGCUUUGGGAGGGCGAGGCGGGUGGAGCACCUGAGGUCAGGAGUUGAGACCGGCCUGGCCAACAUAGUGAAACCCCAUCUCUACUAAAAAUACAAAAAUCAGCCAGGCAUGCUAGUGGGUACCUGUAAUCCCAGCUACUCAGGAAGCUGAGGCAGGAGAAUCAUUUGAACCUGGGAGGCGGAGGUUGCAGUGAGCAAGAUCGUGCCAUUGUACUCCAGCCUGGGCAACAGGAGUGAAACUCAAUCAAAAAAAAGGAACAGGAAUGUUACUAAUUUUAACUACUGCAUUGCAAACAAAUUGUAUUGCAGUAUUUUACCAUCAGAAAAGGAAGGGAAUUGUUUUGUUUGCCUCUGUUAGAUAUUUUAUAUAAACUUGAGGACAUUUUCAUUGGUGAGAUUCGGAAGAGGUGAAGUUUCUUGCAGUACAGGGACGAAGUAGGAAGAGGUGAAGUUUCGUGCAGUACAGGGACGGAGUAGGAAGAGGUGAAGUUUCGUGCAGUACAGGGACGGAGUAGGAAGAGGUGAAGUUUCGUGCGGUGCAGGGACGGAGUAGGAAGAGGUGAAGUUUCGUGCGGUGCAGGGACGGAGUAGGAAGAGGUGAAGUUUCGUGCGGUGCAGGGACGGAGUAGGAAGAGGUGAAGUUUUGUGCGGUGCAGGGACGAAGUUGCUCCCCGCUGGCCACAGGCACUCAAUGAGCUAUUUUACCUAUUUAGGGUUUCUGGGUUGGCCAAGUAACCUCCCAUCCCUUGUGAUAGAUAACUUUAAGUCACACCUUUGGGGGCAAUGUGGGGGGCUCCUGUGCAUCACAUGGAGCACGCUCCCCCAGCACUCUGCAGAGACAGACCCCCAGUCUGACUUAGAGAAAGUAACCAAUGUAGGUGAGGGCCAGGGCACGGUGGCUUACGCCUGUAAUCCCAGCACUUUGGGAAGCCAAGGCGGAUGGAUCACUUGAGGUCAGGAGUUUGAGACCAGCCUGGCCAACAUGGUGAAACCCUGUGUCUACUAAAAAUACAAAAAUUAGCCAACUGUGGUGGUGCGUGCCUGUAAUCCCAGCUAUUCAAGAGGCUGAGGCAGGAGAAUCGCUUGAACCCGGGAGGCGGGGUUUGCAGUAAGCCGAGAUCAUGCCAUUGCAUUCAGUCUGGGUGACAGCGUGAGACUGCAUCUCAAAAAAAAAUUUUUUUUUUUAAAUAUCAAAAUUGAAAACUAGUAUUGUGGUCAUCUGCCUCAAAUUGUGUUACCACACGGGAGACUUAGCAACUCAGCCAGAUUCUUCUAAACACAUUUUUUAUAAUAAAAGUGGUAAAACUACAUUACCAAAAAGAAAAUAGUAAACUUACCUAAAAUCCACUAUGCUAACCCACCCUUUUUUUUUUUUUUUUUUUUUUUUUUUUUUUGAGACAGCCUCACUCUUGCCCGGAGGAGUGGUGCGAUCUCAGCUCACUGCAGCCUCGUCCUCCCAGGCCCAAGCAAUCCUCCCAUCUCAGCCCACUUUGUAGCUGGGACUGUAGGCACUGGCCACCAUGUCCGCCUAAUUUUUCUAUUUUUUGUAGAGACAGGGUUCAAGAGAUCUGCCUGCCUCGGCCCCAGAAAGUUCUGGGAUUGCAGGCGUGAGCCCCCAUUCCCAGCCAUUAACAUCUUACAGGAUUCCCCAGUGGUGGUGGUAGGUGUAACCAUUUUAAUGUACCUACAACUUUUCUAUCCUGCUAUUUGCAUUUUUUGGUUUUUCAUUUAAUAGUUCUCAAGCUGGGAUCCGUGGAACUACUGUGAUGGGCGGUGAUGCUUUGGAAAUGGAAAUUCCCUUAAUAUUAAAAUGAACAUGAAUAUAUUUUGAUUUGCAUAUAUUUUUAAGAUAAAGCAUGAGACUUGUAUAAAGUUCUUUCCUGGCUGGGCGCGGUGGCUCAUGCCUGUAAUCCCUGCACUUUGGAAGGCUGAGGCAGAUGGAUCACCUGAGGUUGGGAGUUUGAGACCAGCCUGACUAACAUGGUGAAACCCCCUCUCUACUAAAAUUACAAAAUUAGCCGGGCGUGUUGGUGCAUGCCUGUAAUCCCAGCUACUCAAGAGGCUGAGGCAGGAAAAUCACUUGAACCCAGGAGGCAGAGGCUGCAGUGAGUGGAGAUUGCAGCAUCGCACUACAGCCUGGGCAACAACAGCAAAACUCCGUCUCAAAAAAAUAAAGUUCUUCCCUUAGAACUAGUCCUGUUGGGCUAGUCUUUCUGGGAUUUUGGUUUACUCUCCUCCACCCAUUGGAAGGGCUUAAAACCGAAUAGCCAGCACCAAGCACAGCUCUGCAUUUUGUAGCUAUCACUGCAGAUGAUUUCUUGAUAGUCCAUCUGGUGGCAAUACAGUGGUCACCCAAGGGGCCAUUGUUUGGGUCUAUGUGAUUUCCCACGUUCUGUUGGAGGCCGGGCGCAGUGCCUCACGCCUGUAAUCCCAGCACUUUGGGAGGCUGAGGUGGGCAGAUCACGAGGUCAGGAGAUCGAGACCGUCCUGGCUAACACGGUGAAACCCUGUCUCUACUAAAAAUACAAAAAAUUGGCCAGGUGCGGUGGCUCACGCCUGUAAUCCCAGCACUUUGGGAGGCUGAGGUGGGCAGAUCUCGAGGUCAGGAGAUCGAGACCAUCCUGGAUAACACGGUGAAACCCCGUCUCUAUUAAAAAUACAAAAAAUUAGCCGGGCAUGGUAGCGGGCGCCUGUAGUCCCAGCUACUUGGGAGGCUGAGGCAGGAGAAUGGCGUGAACCCAGGAGGCGGAGCUUGCAGUGAACCGAGAUAGCCUCACUGCACUCCAGCCUGGGCGAAAGAGCAAGACUCCGUCUCAAAAAAAAAAAACAAAAAAAAAAUUAGCCGGGCGUGGUGGUGGGCGCCUGUAGUCCCAGCUACUCGGGAGGCUGAGACAGGAGAAUGAUGUGAACCCGGGAGGCAGAGCUUGCAGUGAGCCGAGAUUGUGCCACUGCACUCCAGCCUGGGCGACAGAGCAAGACUCCGUCUCAAAAAAUAAAUUAAUUAAUUAAAUUAAAUAAGUGGGUGUUUUAAGUGCUCAGCUUCCUUGGUUCUACCACCUUCUCUCCCUGACCCUCCUUCCCUUUCCCCCUGACCUUGGCCUUUAUUCUAGAACGGAUCUGAAGCAAUAGGAUAUAAAAAAUUCACAACUGCUAAAACAGUGUUCCUUCUAGUGUAAUUUUCACCCUUAGAGACCUGUCUGUAAUAAACAUUAUUUGAAAUGCC